GCUCUGGGCUGUGCGGCACCGCCUCUCCUCGGUGUCUGGGGAGGGACGGAGGGACCGGGCGGGAGAGAGAGAAAGCCUGACCGACCGGCUGGCGAAGAGCUGCAUGCAACCGGUGGGAGGCCGGGCCGGCUGGGUCUGGGGCUCGGGCUCAGGCUCGCACCGUUUCUCGGCAGGUCCCUGGCGGUGAGCGCGGACGGCCCGGAGGCGGCGGCUCUGAGCUGGCAGGCGGAGGGCUGUCUCCUGCGCCCGCCUGCCCGGCGCGGUCCGAGGAUGCGGGGGGGCGAUGCCCGGGGCCAGGGACGCGCUCUGUCACCAGGCGCUGCAGCUGCUGGCCGAGCUCUGUGCCCGUGGGGCCCUGGAGCACGACAGCUGCCAGGAUUUCAUUUACCACCUGCGGGACCGUGCCAGACCCCGGCUCCGCGACCCAGAUAUCUCAGUGAGCCUGCUGACCCUUGUGGUCACUGCCUGUGGUCUCGCUCUCUUUGGCGUGUCUCUCUUCGUAUCUUGGAAACUCUGCUGGGUUCCGUGGCGAGAACGAGGCCUGCCCUCUGGUAGCAAAGACAACAACCAGGAGCCCCUUAACUACAUGGACACAGAGACCAAUGAGCAGGAGAACAGUGAGGACUUCCUAGAUCCUCCCACGCCCUGCCCUGACUCCUCCAUGAAGAUCAGCCACACCUCCCCUGACAUUCCCCUCUCCACCCAGACGGGGAUCCAGGAGAACUGUGCCCAUGGCGUCCGCGUGCAGCGCCAAGUCACAGAGCCAACCUCGUCGGCCCGGCAUAAUUCAAUCCGAAGACAACUCAACUUGUCAAACCCGGACUUCAAUAUCCAGCAGCUUCAAAAACAGGAACAGUUGACUGGAAUUGGUAGAAUUAAACCAGAGUUAUAUAAGCAGAGGUCAUUGGAUAAUGAUGACGGGAGACGGAGUAACAGCAAGGCUUGUGGGAAACUGAACUUCAUUUUAAAAUAUGACUGUGACUUAGAGCAGCUCAUAGUGAAGAUUCACAAAGCUGUCAAUUUGCCCGCCAAGGACUUUUCUGGGACUUCAGAUCCUUAUGUCAAGAUCUAUUUGCUUCCUGAUCGGAAAACAAAACACCAGACUAAAGUUCACAGAAAGACCCUGAACCCUGUGUUUGAUGAAGUGUUUUUAUUUCCGGUUCCCUACAAUGACCUUGAAGCACGGAAGCUUCACUUCUCUGUGUACGACUUUGACAGGUUCUCUCGUCAUGACUUAAUCGGCCAAGUGGUGGUGGAUCACUUCCUAGACUUGGCUGAUUUCCCCAGGGAGUGCAUCCUUUGGAAGGAUAUCGAAUAUGUCACCAAUGACAACGUGGAUCUGGGAGAGCUGAUGUUUUCCCUGUGCUAUCUUCCAACGGCUGGCAGGCUGACCAUUACCAUUAUAAAAGCAAGGAAUUUAAAGGCAAUGGACAUAACAGGAGCAUCAGAUCCCUAUGUGAAAGUCUCGCUGAUGUGUGAUGGCAGACGACUGAAGAAGAGGAAAACAUCCACCAAGAGGAACACCUUGAAUCCUGUUUACAACGAAGCCAUAGUCUUUGAUGUCCCUCCCGAGAACAUUGACCAAAUCCACUUGUCCAUAGCAGUCAUGGACUAUGACCGUGUAGGUCACAAUGAGAUCAUCGGCGUGUGUCAAGUAGGCAACGAGGCUGAGAGGCUGGGCAGAGACCACUGGAGUGAAAUGUUGUCAUAUCCUCGGAAGCCCAUUGCACACUGGCAUUCCCUGGUGGAGGCUCAUGGGUAGAAGGCACUUACCUUGUCUCAGAUGAGACUUUGGACUUUGAACUUCUGAAUUAAUGCUGGAAUGACCUAAGACUUUGGGGGAUUAUUGGGAACACAUGGUUGUAUUUUGCAAUAUGGGAAGAACAUGAGAUUUGGGAGGGGCUGGGGUGGAAUUAUAUAGUUUAAAUAUUUGUCCCUGCCCAAAUCUCAUGUUGAAUUGUGAACCCUAAUGUUGGAGGCAGGACCUGGUGAGAAGUGUUUGGAUAAUAUCCCUCAUGGCUUGGUGCUACCCUCAUGCUAGUGAGGGAGUUCUUGCAAGAUCUGGUUUAAAGUGUGUGGCACCUCCACCCCCCUUGCUCCUGCUCUGCCAUUUGCCACACUGGCUCCCUAUUUGCCUUCUGCCAUAAGUAAAAGCUUCCUGAGACCUCCCCAGAAGCCAAGCAGAUGUCAGUGCCAUGCUUCCUGUAUAGCCUGCAGAACUGUGAACCAAUUAAUCUGCUUUUCUUUAUAAAUUAUCCAGUCUUGGAUAUUUCUUUAUACCAAUGCAAGAAUGGACUAAUACACCAAUCAAGAAAGUAAAUACCAUCCAAAGGGAUUAAGAUUGACUAUAAAUUUUAAAAUAUGAACAUUCUGAAUUUUUCUUCCUGUUAUUAAUGCUUAAUGAAGUCCUGGAAAUGGGAACGGAGAAGUGGAUCCAAAUACAUCCACAUCUGCGUGUGCUUUUUGCUGGGGCUUUAUCUGCAUUCUCUCUCUGCUAUGGUCUGAGUGCUUGCAUCCUCCCAAAAUUCAUAUGUUGAAACCUAAUCCCCAAUGUGCUGGUAUUAAGAGAUGGGAAACAAUUAGGUUAUGAGGGCUCUGCCUUCAUGAAUGGGAUUAGUGCCCUUAUAAAAGAGGCCCAAGGAAACUUGUUUGCCCCUUCUACCAUACGAGGACACAGAAUGAUGGCCCCAUCCAUGAGGCAGAGAGCUAGCACUCACCAGACACCAAAUCAGCUAGCACCUUAUCUUGGACUUUCCAGCCUCAAGGACUGUGAGCAAUAAAUUUCUGUCAUUUAUAAAUUAUCCAAUCUAAGAUAUUUUGUUAUAGUAGCCCAAAAGGACUAAGACAUCCCCCUUAAUGACUGGAGUCAGAAUCACAUCAAAAAAUAAGGCUGAGUUGGAGCCAGCAACAUUUAUUCACAAGAGAAAGACAGGAAUUGGACUGGCUGCAGAGAGGCCCACAGAGUCAGAGACCAUCCACCUCAGCUACAGCACAGGGCUCAGCACUGUAUUUCUGGUGUUAGUGCUAUUCUCAAUUCUGUCCCUAGUUCCUGCUACUGAGGAACUCCAUACACAGCAGGACAGUCUUCUGCUGUGCCAUGAAUUCAAACACAAUCUGUAAAGACAGUGAAGGAAGCUACGUCUGUGCUUAGGUGCUUUAGAGAAUUAUCGGCUUGCAGUAAUAAGAGAAAUGUCUGGGCUGGGUAGUCCUCAAAGACUCCCAUGUGGUUCAAGAUAACAAAAUAUAAAGGCUGAGCAUCUCGUGCUCCCAACCUAGUUCUAAGGCGUCUAUGGAGGGAUAGUGAGUGGGGCUCUCUAUGGCAGUGAUUGCCUCUAAUGAAGGAACCAAAAGCCAGGCAGGGAUUAGGGUGGGCUUCUGGUUUUAGAAAACAUGAUGGUAGAGCUCUUCAUAGGAAGUUUUUAAGAUCAAGGUAGGAUCCUGCUUGGAGGAUCGUAGCCUGGCAGUCUGGAUCAGCCUGGUGGUGGAGGUGAAGGGUGUGGAAGCUGGACUCACUUUGGCACACAAAGUUCAGGAAUGAGUUGACAACCAAGGCCCCGUGGCUAUGGAAGAUCGUAUCACAUGACCCCAAAGUAUGGCAGGGCAGCCAGCGGAGCAGUUCUACCUCUCUACCUUGGGCCUGCAGGGUGACAUCAACAUUGAUAACAUUGAAGGCAUGAUGUUGUCAAUAUUUAUUAUAAGCACACUUAUAAUCUUAAAUUUGCACUUUAUCCUAGCCUCCGUGGUGCCUAUUGUAUUUAUGGGUGAGUAGUUGGAGGUGACAGAAUAUAAUCUUUCAGUUGCAUUUAAAGUUUUAUGUUUCUUAAAGUUACAGAAAGUUCGUUCCCAGGACUGGGGCUAAUGGCUCUUCUCCUGCUCCUUACAGAUAAUGUGGCACUUCCAUUGCCUAGUAUGGAACCAAUAUAUCACAUGAAUGUGCACUUACCUAGAACUAGUCUUAUAUCAGGAAUGAGGAUCCAGGGAUCCUUGCAAAGAAAGAAAUAAUAAUUCAGAGAAACCCUACACUCUCAGGAUAAGAAGGGGGAAAAUCAAGGUUCCCGCCAUCAACCAAAUGGUUUGAGUCCAGGCAGAAUCUAAACCAUCACUCACAGUGCGCCAUCUGCUCCAGCACCAGCCCUCCUGAUUCUUUUGCAGGUCAGCAGGCAUGAAAGAGUUAAUAGCAAAGGCCAUGAGAAACUUGCUCGCUGUUAUAGAGAAAUCACUUUUAGUUCCAGUUGCUGCUGCCAGAGGAGAUGCUUGAGAGCAAGAUAGGAAAUAAUAAGGAAGAAAAGGACUUUUGAAUCACAUGAGAGUCUUCGAGGACUACUCAGCCCAGAUGUUCCUCUUAUUGCUUCAAGCCAAUAAUUCUCUAAAGCCCCCAUGCACAGAUGUAGCUUCCUUCACUGUCUUUACAGAUUGUGUUUGAAUUCAUGGCAGACCAGGAGACUGUCCUGCUGAGUAUGGACUUCCUCAGUAGCAGGAACUAGGGACAGAAUUAAGAAUAAUAUAACAUAUAUGAAAUAACUGUAUUCCAUAACUGGAAAUACAGUGCUGAGCCCUGUGCUAUAGCUGAGGUGGAUAGUCUCUGCACUUUAAAAGAGAGUCUUUGAGCAACUGCAGACAAAGACUGAUAUAACUUCUUGAUUAGAAAAUCAGCUGAAAGGCCGGGCGCAGUGGCUCACGCCUGUAAUCCCAGCACUUUGGGAGGCUGCGGGGAGUGGAUCACUUGAGGUCAGGAGUUCAAGAUCAGCCCGACUAACAUAGUGAAACCCUGUUUGUACUAAAAAUACAAAAAUUAGCUGGGCAUGGUGGUGCAUGUCUGUAAUCCCAGCUACUUGGGAAGCUGAGGCAGGAGAAUUGCAUGAACCCAGGAGGCAGAGGUUGCAGUGAGCCGAGACUGUGCCAUUGCACUCCAGCCUGGGCAACAGAGCCAGACUUCAUCUAGAAAAAGAAAAAAAAAAAUCAGCUGAAAAGACCAGAAGAGAACUCCAUGAGACAGGGAAUAAUGGUGAGCCAGGACUAUUAUAGGAGAAACAGAUCUGGGCCAGAUUCAGGACUUCACCCAUUCCAAUUUUAGAGAGGAGGGCUUGGAAUUUAAGGACUGAGCCCUUCCACCAUCACUAUCCACUCCAUGCUAAGAGAACAUUAGGUGGCCUCUGUUUUUAAGGCUCUGUGCUGCUGAGCAGGACAUGCUUGCUAUUGAGGUGGGUAGGAUAGUAGGUUACCUAUAAGGUUCCUUCCAGGCAGUAAAGAAACUGAAGAAAGAGCAGGUUAGGAAAAGGGAGAGAAGUGUUGGUGCAGCAGCCAGCCACAGGGAAAGGAAUUUGGUGGCCUUGGAGGGAGGGAAAGUGGGGACAGUAUCUUCAGUAGGAUUAACAUGGAUUUGCAUUUGAAUUGUAAAAUGAGAAGUUGCUUAGUCGGAUCUCAGACUGAGGGUCCAUGGUGCUCCUAUAUGUUUCUAGAUUAUUUGUAAUAUGCUGUUUAUAUGCAUGUAUAUGUACAAAUGUAAGAGCUCUUAGCAAACUUAAGCAUACACACAAAGACUUAAAUUACUUGUUUAAUACAGUGGUGUCCAGUUGGUUUUUUUGUUUGUUUGUUUGUUUGUUUUUGGCCAAAUUCUUUGAUGAAGUCAAAUCUAAUUUGAAAGUUGAAGGUCUAAAACAGAUAAAUGCAAGAGCUACUGUGAUCGAAGCAGACAAAUUGAGGAGAGCAAAAUCAUUUAAUCAAAGAGGAAGACGUGACCCAGCUCAACUUCCUGGUGGACGACCUCAGCUGUGCUGUUGUUACUAGUGUCUAACAGGAAGAGGAACCUAAUUACAGCUCAGCCACUUCGAGCUGCUGAGCUUGAGCAAAUUAUCUCAUCUCUCUGAGGAUUCAUUUCCUCUUCUGUAAAAUGGGGAUAUCAGUAGCUAGUUUUAGAUAACUGUGUGAGGAUGAUUAAAUGAUACAACAUACCUGAAAGCACCUAGCAUAAUAUCUGGUGAAAGCAGUGAAAGACGCUGGACAAGUGUUUGUUUCCUUUCUGCAGCCAAUUAAGAUUCUGGGAAACUGUAACUCUACCCAGGCUUUCCAGUAGCUUAUUUUUUAUUGUUCUAUUGUAGUGCUUAAAUAAGGAUAACUUUUCCAGAGAUAGCCUAAGUUUCUCAUUUCUCUGGCUCUUGGAAUUUCCAGUGCUUCACAAAGACUUUAGUGUUAAGAAUGUAAGGUGUAGCACAGUAUUUCAAUAAGUCCCCAGUUCUACAUGGAAGGGAGCAGUGUGCCACAAAUGUUCUUGGCAUUGAUUCACAUUUAGAUAUACAUUUCAGUCAUGACAUGGACAUAGAUAUAAAACUGAAACAAAAGUUUCACGAAAUUAAUAAACAUAACGUGAUGCACUUUUUAAUUUUUUUUCAUUAAAAAUAGACUACUGGUCACAAUCAUUAAAUUAAUUUCACAAACCCAUAAUGGGCCACUGCCCAUUAUGGAUUCAAUAAACACUGUGUGAUAUGCACUUUGAAAACGACCACUGUAUUUGGAUCCAGUGUGGGAGUGAUAAGAAGGAAUAUGGACUCAUCACCAACUGCCCAUAUUUUUAGGACCCUCUAGAGUGAUUUUUUUUUUUUCUGAAAAGCCAGAAUUCUAAGAUUGUCAUCACAUAUUUUCACCGGAAAUUAAUGUCAUUCCUUGGUUUUAGCUUCUCUGCAUAGAACACUACAUGCCUGAGUUUGUGUUGCCACAUUUGCAUGGGCACAAAUAAGUUAUUUUUACCACAAAUAUUUAACCUUCCAGUUUGAAGCUGUGCUGUGCUUAGCCUAAACAGCAUAGAGAGACCAACUGUGUUUAUAAUUAAAGAAAAAUGCUGUGCAAAGCCACAGAAGGAAGGAAGAGGCAAUUCUUGUUGGAGGUAUGUGUCACUGCUUUCAAGGGGUUCCCUGAGGUGCUUGACUCCACACGGACUCUUUCAUUCCUGCUAGGUUGCGAAUACUACACCAAGUGCUGUGGACAGAGAGAUGUAGAUGAAGCACCGGCCUGUAAAGAGUCUGGUGGGGGAGUCUGACAGGAAAUUGUUCCAGUGUAAUAGUGUCAAUCAUAUAAUUGGUGGUUUCAAAUUUUGUAUAGAUGGGAGAGUUGUCAGCCUUCCACAGGGGAGAGGGUGGUGACCAGAGACACAUGCUGACCCCACUUGAGCAGGCUCUUGGAAAUACGGAAAUCCUUCCCAAUAGGAAAGGAAAGGUUGAAGAUACAAGAGAGGGAGGGGAUAACUGCUGUGCGGGCUUUGACCUGGAGAUACGUGGCCCAGCUCUUCUCACAGAGCACACAGGAUGCUCUGCCCUCCUAUAACAGGCACAUCAGGGCCCCAUCUCAUCUUUGUGGCAUAUGGAAGCAAAUGUUACUCCAUGGGCAGGAUUCAGAGGCAGCCAUGUGCUGCUCUUAGUACAAGGGCAGAGGACCCAGCAUUAAUGCAGUGCUUUCUAUCACCUUUCCCAACUACCAGAACUUUGGCCCACCCAUCUGCCUCCUCUCUCCCAGGUCUCUUGGUGCCCAGGUUUUCUCUGCAUACUUGCUGCACUCUCUGGUGUCCUGGAAGCAGCUCUGCCCUCUUCCAACCUGGCUCAGCCUUGAAAGGGCCCCUUUUUUCACAUUGGUGCAGGUAGGUCUUUUGCCACCAUCCAAGCCUUGUUCCUAUUCUUCUAUCAACUUCCAUCAGCUUGUAUGGAACAACACAUCCCCUCCCCAGUGCUCUGCUGUGCACAUUGAAACUGCCCUUCUCAGAUCAGAGCCCCGCCCCUGUCAUCCCAUGCACCUCCUACAUCCCGCCCCUGACUCUUGGAUGUCGCACUUCUGUUCAGACUUCAUCUCUGAUUUCAGCAUUAGAUACAGAAGCUUUUUCCUGCUAAGUCCUCUCCUCCCAGAUCUAAUUCACAGCCAGCAAAUCCAGCUGUGGGCAGUCUUUGAGCAUUUACUCUAAAGCUCUAAAGGACCCAAAGGUGAUGCAAGAGCCACCUCCCUCCACUCAGAAAGGAAACACUCACUGUGUCCAUUUGGCUUCAAUCAGACAAACCCAAGACAUUCAGAGGGAUGAACCGACCUGAAAAAUAUCCCUAAAAACCUACUUUAACAGAAAGCACAAAGUUUCAGGAAAGAAUGGAAGAAAUUAUAGAAACUGGAAUUAUACAAACUAGUAGGGGCAUGGAGGCAUGCACACAGCUUAGAAGAGAAGGAAGUCACUCUAUCUGCUUCAGUGUCAUGAUGGUGUGAGACCUUGACCAAGAAUGUAAAUUUAAACCUUCUGGGAAACUUUGCUGUGCUCCAGCAGACAAAGAAAAGGAGGCUGAGGAAAGUGUCAGAGCCAAGGUGGACUGAUAGGAGGGAGGAGCGUGUCUAAUCUCAAGCAGCCUGCUCUGGUGCAAGGACACAGCCAGGAACACUGGAACUCAGGAACACUGGGACACACCUGCCAAGGCUGCCAGAGAAGCAUUUCAUGGGAGUGGACCCCAAGGCCAAGUCACAGGAAUUGCAGUCAAGCAACAUCAAGUCAAAAGACAGGCUGCAAGGUAGGAGGUGAAGACAUGAGCAGAAGGCUGGAGAGAUUGAGCAGAGACUUCAAAGCUGGAAAUCAGACUUUAGCAAAUGAGAGGUCAGGACAAGGAAGCAGGGGUAUGUUACAGAGCAGACAAGAGGCAGAGCCCACCCUGGAACAUGUUAUUCACGGUGCCUACCAUCUCAGCCUCCCCUGCAUGCAUGUACAACUUCACCCCUAAUAUCUGUUGAACAAGCAGCCCUAACCACCGAGGUUUGUAAAAUGUCCUGGCCACAGGUGAUUGGAUCAAGAUGGGGACAUGCUCCCAGAAAGCUGUUUAUGGGCUGUCCAGUGACUUAUGACAUGGCCUGGCACCCCAAGGUGGGUUGGGUCAAUUAGAUUAUGCCACCAAACUUAGAAAUGUCAGGGAAAUGAGGCAAUCAUAGUUCCUUCUCUUGGGCUUCUCUAAGAAUCCAUUUCUAUUAUUGUUCCAUAAGUACUUUAUUAUAGAACACCAUAAGCACUCCCAUCUAGACUCUCACUGAACUGCCUUGAUUCAGCCUCUGUUCCCGUACAACCUGAAGACUCACCAGAACACGUAUGGACUUGCAGCUGUCCAGAAGCACAGUGAUGAAUGGUGUGUUUGGCCACUCCAUUUGUUUUCACAUAGUUUCCCACAGUUUAGAAGUGCUGAAGAUGAGACCUUAAAAGAGUUGGAACCCCCCUGAGUAGAAAAGAAGCUGGAAUUAGCAAAAUAACACAAAUAGGCAUGAGAUUCAUCCUACUGGGAGGAAGUCACCCUUACAAGAAGAGAAGCACAAAUGAGGAGGACCCCCGCUCACUUAAGUGUAAAAAAAAUGCUGUGUUUAGAAGCUCAGUAAGAUCACAGUUAGUGACUUUUCCCAGAGGGGGUAUAAGAAGUUUCAUGGAGACCCAAAAGGUCUGAUGGCAAGAUACCUUCCCAAUGUUGAGUAAGGCGCCAUAGUCUGCCAAAACUCUUCAAAGCCACUGCUUCUCAUGGACAUAAACGUUCCACCAGAAGUGAACAUGGUGGUAUUUUUUGAGUGGAACAAUGAAAGAUGUGAGAAUACAGGUGGUAUUUUCAUUGCUUCUUCCUACUGCCCUUUGGAACUCUGGAAGACUGAAGAAUAUCUAAAGAUGAUCAGUAGUGGACUUACAAGAAUAGGUUGAUAUUUAGAAUGAGGUUCUGAAACACAGCUUAAGAUACCAGAAUAAAUCAUUCUAGCCAUGAGUGCAGAGAAUCUUACAAAGACAUGGGGGACUAUGUUGCUUAGCGACUGAUCAGCUGAUCUCAUCAAGAGGAUUUAAAAACUGAUACCAGGAGGAAGAGUAAGACAACACAAUAAAAUAGACAACCCACAAGACCAGUUGCUAUGAAUGACAUCCAGUGGGAUGUGGAAAAAAAGGGUUCCAGGACAGGAGGUUUCCAGUGAUUCACAGGAGAUAAGAUUGAAUCCUAGAUGUAAGUGAUGGCCAUGGCCUUGGGUGUCCUAAUGCAUCCUGCAGAGAGAACAAACAGAAUAACCCAGGACAAUGAUCACAGCCUUGUAGAUAUAACUGGCACCCAAACAUGUCAACAGACCACUUAGAAGCAGACAGAUUAAUGUGCUAUACAUGCCUGAAGAGCUGUGUACCUAACGUUGAAAGCUCAUUGAUACACAUAUUGUGGGCAUUAGCAGAAAUGAGCCUGCCAGGGAAAUAUGACAGGUGGAGAGGUGAGACUCCUAAAACAAAUCAAAGCACUAGUACAGAGAUAAAAAUCCAGUGGUGAGGGAGAAACCCACUGAGGAGAUGUUUCCUGGAAGUCUUCUUUGGUUAAAGACAAAGUGAAAACUUCUCCAGUUGCUUUGCUACAAGUAUUAGAAUACUUUUGAUGUAAUGAACAGAAAUCCUGACACAAACUAGAUUGAACAAAGAAACUGUAGCAUCUGGACAAAGGGUCUAGAGAUAGGAUUGUAGAUUCCAUGGUUAAGGAUGGGGGGUUCCGGGAUUGUAGAUUCUGUGGUUAAUGAUGGUAUCAGGAACACCAGUUCUUCCCAGGCUAUUGGGCCAUCCUUCCUUCCUUUCUGUUCAUCUUCAGGUUGGUCGCAAGAUGGAUGCAGGUCUAGGCAUUGCAUCCAGACAUGAAAGUAGCCACAGGAAAACGCACUUCUUGUAGCUCUCUGUUAAGAGCAAGGAAAAAAUUAUUCAAGUGCCCAGCAAACUGGCUCCUUACACAUCAUGGCCAGAAGUAUGCCAAUUUUUGAAGCAGUCACUGGCAAAAGGAAUGGGACUGUGUGGGCCCAACAGGUUCAGCCCUGGAGAUGGAUCCCUUCUUCUGGGACACCAAGAAAAACACCAUCCCCUUCUCCCCUGGCAAUACCCAGCCAACCUUCCAGCUAUGACUCUCCCCCACAGGCACCCUGUUUCUUCUCAUGACAACUCUGCACUCCAUUAUCCACCUCCUGGGAGCAAACCAUUUUGUAGCCUAUUCCAAAAAGCUCAAGCCAGCACAGACACCACAGGGCAGCAAACGAAAUCUGAAUCUCAAAGCUUGCCAGACCAGCAGCGCCCACUGAGAAACUCUCCAGAUAAGAGAUGAUCCCAGGAACCCCACCGCCUCCUGCCAUGUCUCUGCACAUGCCAUCAACGCUCUGCUCUCAGUGAAAAUGGCUGAGGGGAGGAGCUUUUCCUCUACAGACCCAACGCUGCCAUUUCCCACCCCUGUGGUGGGACUCGAAGAGGGGCUGGAGAACACGUCUCCACACACAUACAGCUGUGGCCUGCUUUUGGCUCUCUCCUCCCACUCUUCUGCAGCGCAAACCAGGGUGGAGGAUGGUGUCAGACCCGUCUUUCGGAACACUUGUCAUUUCAAGAACCAGAGAGGCAAAGCCCUUCAGGCAUGUUUGGAGUCCCAGAGAGCUCAGCACAGGACUCGUGCUGCCAACACUGUGACUCUAGACUAUCUUGCUGGGAAUCGGGAUUUCAGCUCCUCUUUCCACACACCUUCACCCCCAGCACUGGGCACCCACUUCUGCAGCUCCCCACUCAAAUUGGUCCCCCUCCUUUAUGACACUGGGCUUCUCUGGAUUCCUGUCAGCCGUUUUCUCCAGUCCUGGGGCUCUCAAUAUCUCCAAAUACUCACAUGGGUAAUGGGUUCCUUGACCCAAUGACAAGCAUCUGUCUCUCAAAGAGCAGUAGGCCUUUCCUAGGGCCUCUGCCAUCAGCUCUGCUGCCCUUUGCUGCCCUCCCCUGGCCAUUGACAUCACUGCAGGUAACUCUUCAGGACUCUGAUGGGUUCAUUGAUACAUCCAUUCAAAAAAAAAGUAUUUAGGGGCCCUGUGUACCACGCGAUGUCCAGACACUGAGGAUUCAGUGAUAAAAACACAUGGCGCCUGCCUUCCAGGAGUACACAGUCUAGUGAGGAAAAUGAGAGAGAGGGAGAAAAGCAGAGAGAGAGAGAGAUAAUGAAUGAAUGAGAAUGAGAAUGAAAGAAGGAAUGAGAAUGAGAGAGAGGACUUUUUGAAUGGGAAUGAGUGGAUUCUGGUGUGCCCUUGUGGAAGUCUAGAUUUGCUCAUUGUUCUGCAGACCCGACUGCCUAACAUGUUCACCUGAAAAGGAAUCCCCUGGCCUCCCCUUUGGAAGUGGAGUUGGAGAAUUUAUUUUAAACCGAAUAUUUCUGAGCAAGUGCAAAGCACCCUACCUGGCACUGAGGUAUAAUGGGGAAAUGCUGGUCCCAUCCCCCACAGAAUUUACAAUCUGGCUGAGGAAAUAGACAUAAGAAAAUAAUUAGAUUGUUUAAUAACAGUUAUGGUGUUACCUGGUACUGUAUUCUGUCUUAGUCAUACCUAGCAAGAGCUCCACACAGCAAGGAUAGGGCAUGGGGUCCAUGUUUUAGGGGGUAGAAGGAGUGAACCACAGAGAGCACAGCCCGUGCACAUGGUAGGCACCUCAGGAAGUGCUGAAUGCAUGAAAGAGGCUGCGCAGCAGACAAGGCUCCUGGGAGCCAAGGCCAGUGUCUCCAGCCAGCUCAGCUGAAAUCAGCAGCUCAUGUGCUCCGUUCUUCACCUUCAGCAUGCCCACUUCAUCCUGAAACUCUCUUCUACCCACCACCUCAUCUCCAGAUGCAGAUCCUAAUGUCCCAGACAGGACUGUUGGCAGGUUCCAAGUCAAGUGAAGGAUAAUUCAAGAGCCACAGUCCAAUAGUGCAGGAGCCAUAUCUGCUCUAUUUGCCAUUGUAUACCCAAUCCUUCACAUAGUACCUGGCACAUAGGAGGUACUCCAUAAUUCUGUGACGGUUGUUGAAUGAAUGCAUGGAUUUUGCAUAACUAUUCAGGCAAGAGCUUAGCUUCUAUAGAGAAUUUGGUCAUGAUUGGAUUCAUUUGAUCAGUGGAAGCAGCCAUUCCAGUUUACUAUAGAAGUAACAUUCCAGUUACUAUAGAAGUAGAUUUAGAACCUAAUUUGGCCUAUUGGCUACAAAAAGGGUACAGACUCUGAGUUGUAGUGAGACUGCCAGUCUACCUGCAGGUCGAUGAGGGCUCCUCCAUCCUCCCUGGGCUGAGAUUUAAUAGUGCCUCUUUUUGCUCAGCCUGCUCUCUAAUCCUCAGGGUGAGAGAUCAGUAUGAACUGACAGGUCUGAGAAAUCUUCCUAGGGGAGGAAGAAGGGUUUCCAGCUGCAAGGAGAGAGCAGCGUGCAGUGACAGUGAGGCACCAGGAUGUAGAACAAUGCUGCCAGAACAUAUUCCCUGAGGUUUGGGAAUGAACUUCUUCAAGGGCUGUGCUCCCUUUUUGAUGGGUCCUAGUGGGCCUCUGUGCUGGUCGUGACCGACUUUUCUUCAAUGAUCCAGUGGAGGCUGCAAUGUAUUUUGCUUAAAACUACAGCUGGUUUAUAAUUUUGGCCUCAGACAGUAAUUACAGCUGCUGGGGCUCCUUGGAGAGAUAAUUACGGAAAGAAUUCAGCAUAUUCAUUUUAUCUACACACUUAACCAUCAAUUAAAUCAUUACCAUCUAAUCCUAUUCCAGAGUCUAGAAAUGUUCUGUGAAUAUAUAAUUUUGAAGGCACUGAAGUUUGUUUUCAGAUGGUUUUAAGUGAAAAAUUGCCCAAUUUCCAUAGCCAAUGGAGGCUUUCUCUAUGAAAGCAGAGCCGAGAGUAUCUCCUGGCUUGUGGUUGCUGCCUCCCUGGGGGCCUGCACCACAUAAAGGGCCAAGCAGGAAUGGAUUGAUAGGCGGGAGCUGGGACUUUGCCUUUGAUCUCCCAUGGAGUUUGUGAUUUUCCAAAGCAGGAUUAGCACUGGGACUUAGAGGUCAGUGGCUGGAGACAGACAAGAGGGUGGCUUGUUUUGCCAAGGAGCUUCCAGGAGAGUCUUCCCCUGCUGGGAUUCUGCUAGGGCCCUGGGCUGUCAUCCACUUAUCAAAGUCAGGAUGGGGUCUUUUCACUUUGGGAACCCAGGAGAGAGUGUGGUAUUUAAAAGCAUGAGUGCUGGAGCUGGCUUCACUUUCUGGCUUUGCCAUUUUUGAGUUGUGUGUCCUUGAGCAAGUUUCUAAAUUCCUCUAAACCUCAGGUUAUUCCACUCUUUAGCAACACAACAAUAGAUCCUACCUCACAGAGCUGUGUGAGACUUAAAUGAAAAAAUGAAUGUAACAUGUUUAACACAGCAUCUGGAACUUAAUGGAUGCUAGGUAAACUUUGAUAAUUGAUAUUAUUCAACAUACAUGUAUGUACAAGAAAAGGAGAGAGGCAGAAGGGAGAAAUCAAAUGUCCAAAAAUGUGCUUCAGCGGGAACCAGGGCCUCUGAAAGCAUAUGUGGCAUGGGCUGGGACUGCCCCUGGGCUUCACUGUCCAGCCUUGGACUCCACGGCUGCUCUCUGCUCUCUCUGACCUUGACUUCCCUUGGGGAUGGUCGCCUGGGAACCUCUGACUGCAGUCCCCCUCUGUACCCCUCCUCCCUGACCCUACCCUCUCAUGGCUCCAGCCUGGUGCUCCUCCAAAAACCUUGCUGCACUGCUGGUACCCUGAAUAUGCCUGUUCUCCUCCUACACUUCCAACCAUCCUUUUCUCUCUUUCUCAUGGGCUUUCGCUGGCUGACGGUGGGAUAUAGUCAUGCCUCAAGUUUCUGACCUAAGUCACUUUUUGUUUUUUUCUACACCACACAAAGCAGCAUCUGGGAAGACGGCCCACAGGGAUGCAACUGCUUCCUGGCCUCUUUCAGCCAGGGAGGCAAUUUUUCUAAUAGACAGGAGUCUUGGGCUGAAUCCUCUUCAGACUGUUCCUAACACUGGAAUCCCAGAGGCACUGUCUAUACAGUGGGGCCCUGAGGAAGUCUCCUCUUUGUGAGCUGACUCUUCCAGAUGGCUGCACUAGUCCUCUGGCCAGUGUUUGGGCUCAGACAAUCCUACCCUACUGUACACGGUACGUGGCUCCUGUGCUGAAGUUACUAAAAAGCCCAGCUCUUGUAGCUGGCAUAGAACUGGUCACAAGGCUGGCUUUUGCCCUGGCAUAAGCCGCGUCUAUGUGGGAGCCCCAAGCUGGGAACCAGCCCCAGGCACAGCAUCAAGUCCACGUGGCAGACUUGCCUGAAAAACACCCACUUGACCUUAUAGUUGUGCCUAUCACCGAGCCAAGGGCUGCAAAGGAAAUGAAAAGCUCCCAACUGCUGAAAUCAUGGAGCUGGAAUAUCAAGUCUCUAUGUUCAAGGAUAAUCAUGGUUAUCGUUGGAAGGACUGUACAGUGAAGAUUAAUUUUUAACCUCCUCUGAGAGUUGUAAGAAUUAAAUAAGUUAAUAAAUGCAGAACACUUACAAGA